AUAGUUCUCCCUGAGUGAGACUUGCCUGCUCCUCUGGCCCCUGGUCCUGUCCUGUUCUCCAGCAUGGUGUGUCUGAAGCUCCCUGGAGGUUCCUACAUGGCAAAGCUGACAGUGACACUGAUGGUGCUGAGCUCCCCACUGGCUUUGGCUGGGGACACCCGACCACGUUUCUUGCAGCAGGAUAAGUAUGAGUGUCAUUUCUUCAACGGGACGGAGCGGGUGCGGUUCCUGCACAGAGACAUCUAUAACCAAGAGGAGGACUUGCGCUUCGACAGCGACGUGGGGGAGUACCGGGCGGUGACGGAGCUGGGGCGGCCUGACGCUGAGUACUGGAACAGCCAGAAGGACUUCCUGGAAGACAGGCGCGCCGCGGUGGACACCUACUGCAGACACAACUACGGGGUUGGUGAGAGCUUCACAGUGCAGCGGCGAGUUGAGCCUAAGGUGACUGUGUAUCCUGCAAGGACCCAGACCCUGCAGCACCACAACCUCCUGGUCUGCUCUGUGAAUGGUUUCUAUCCAGGCAGCAUUGAAGUCAGGUGGUUCCGGAACAGCCAGGAAGAGAAGGCUGGGGUGGUGUCCACAGGCCUGAUUCAGAAUGGAGACUGGACCUUCCAGACCCUGGUGAUGCUGGAAACAGUUCCUCGAAGUGGAGAGGUUUACACCUGCCAAGUGGAGCACCCAAGCGUGACGAGCCCUCUCACAGUGGAAUGGAGAGCACAGUCUGAAUCUGCACAGAGCAAGAUGCUGAGUGGAGUCGGGGGCUUUGUGCUGGGCCUGCUCUUCCUUGGGGCCGGGCUAUUCAUCUACUUCAAGAAUCAGAAAGGGCACUCUGGACUUCACCCAACAGUGCUCUCAUCUGAGUCCUUGAAAGAGAGGAAAAGAAGCUGUUAGUGGAACCAGGUCUGAAAACAACACUUUCCUCUCUCUCUGCAGGACUCGUGAGCUGAAGUGCAGAUGACCACAUUCAAGGGGGAACCUUCUGCCCCAGCUUUGCAUGAUGAAAAGCUUUCCUGCUUGGCUCUUAUUCUUCCACAAGAGAGGACUUUCUCAGGCCCUGGUUGCUACCGGUUCAGCAACUCUGCAGAAAAUGUCCAUCCUUGUGGCUUCCUCAGCUCCUGCCCUUGGCCUGAAGUCCCAGCAUUGAUGGCAGUGCCUCAUCUUCAACUUUAGUGCUCCCCUUUACCUAACCCUACGGCCUCCCAUGCAUCUGUACUCCCCCUGUGUGCCACAAAUGCACUACGUUAUUAAAUUUUUCUGAAGCCCA